AGGCAGGCAGGCGCGCUCGGGCGAGGUAGGAGCGAUGUGGCCUGGGAACGCCUGGCGCGCCGCACUCUUCUGGGUGCCCCGCGGCCGCCGCGCACAGUCAGCGCUGGCCCAGCUGCGUGGCAUUCUGGAGGGGGAGCUGGAAGGCAUCCGCGGAGCUGGCACUUGGAAGAGUGAGCGGGUCAUCACGUCCCGUCAGGGGCCGCACAUCCGCGUGGACGGCGUCUCCGGAGGGCCUGGCACUGUCAUCUUUCCAGGCCUGCCCUUGCCCCACCUGAGCUGCUGUAUCCAUCUCCUCUCCUUCACCUCAGGAAUCCUUAACUUCUGUGCCAACAACUACCUGGGCCUGAGCAGCCACCCUGAGGUGAUCCAGGCAGGUCUGCAGGCUCUGGAGGAGUUUGGAGCUGGCCUCAGCUCUGUCCGCUUUAUCUGUGGAACCCAGAGCAUCCACAAGAAUCUAGAAGCAAAAAUAGCCCGCUUCCACCAGCGGGAGGAUGCCAUCCUCUAUCCCAGCUGUUAUGACGCCAACGCCGGCCUCUUUGAGAGCAGGGCGCUGGUCCAGCCCGGCACUGAGACACGGGGGCCCCAGAGAGAAGCACAGAACACCUUGCCUCUCUACCCAGAGGAGCGCCCUGGCUGGCAGUACAGUUUUUUGAUUUGCUGGAGUCCCGGUCAAGGGAGAAGCCCAGGGUGGUUAAAUGAUGGCUCUACGCUCACUGCCUCCCUCCAGGCCCUGCUGACCCCAGAGGACGCAGUCCUGUCGGACGAGCUGAACCAUGCCUCCAUCAUCGACGGCAUCCGGCUGUGCAAGGCCCACAAGUACCGCUAUCGCCACCUGGACAUGGCCGACCUAGAAGCCAAGCUGCAGGAGGCCCAGAAGCAUCGGCUGCGCCUGGUGGCCACUGAUGGGGCCUUUUCCAUGGAUGGCGACAUCGCACCCCUGCAGGAGAUCUGCUGCCUCGCCUCUAGAUAUGGUGCCCUGGUCUUCAUGGAUGAAUGCCAUGCCACUGGCUUCCUGGGGCCCACAGGACGGGGCACAGAUGAGCUGCUGGGUGUGAUGGACCAGGUCACCAUCAUCAACUCCACCCUGGGGAAGGCCCUGGGUGGAGCAUCAGGGGGCUACACGACAGGGCCUGGGCCCCUGGUGUCCCUGCUGCGGCAGCGCGCCCGGCCAUACCUCUUCUCCAACAGUCUGCCACCUGCUGUCGUUGGCUGCGCCUCCAAGGCCCUAGAUCUGCUGAUGGGGAGUAACACCAUUGUCCAGUCUAUGGCUGCCAAGACCCAGAGGUGCGACUCCCAGCAGGGCAGGCUCGGGGGCGGAGAGACGUGGUUCCGUAGUAAGAUGGAAGCUGCUGGCUUCACUAUCUCGGGAGCCAGUCACCCCAUCUGCCCUGUGAUGCUGGGUGAUGCCCGGCUGGCCUCUCGCAUGGCGGAUGACAUGCUGAAGAGAGGCAUCUUUGUCAUCGGGUUCAGCUACCCCGUGGUCCCCAAGGGCAAGGCCCGGAUCCGGGUACAGAUCUCAGCAGUGCAUAGCGAGGAAGACAUUGACCGCUGCGUGGAGGCCUUCGUGGAAGUGGGGCGACUGCACGGGGCACUGCCCUGAGCUCUGGGUAAGGACGAGAAGAGCCAAGGUCCGCCUACUGCCACAGGGUCAAAGGAGGUUUUCGAUCAGCCCAGACCAGAGGCUCUGAGCCCUGAACCAAAGUCCCAGAGCUGGGCUGGGACGUGACCUGUGCUGAGGGCUGUGAGAAUGUGAAACAACAGUGUGAAAAUUGGCUGUGA